GCUUCCGGCUCGGCCAUUGUUUUUGGUCUAACGGGCAGUAGAGUGUCCGGCUUCGGUGCCGAGUGCCACCGCGAGUGGGCCGAGACGCGGAGGGAGGCGCGGCCGGAGCUCGGGUCGCCGACGCUGGCCAGGACCGCGCUUCUUCCCGGCGGCAGGCGGCGCGGUCCCCGUGACUCUCAGAAGCCGCCCGAUGUAGAGCCGCUUCUUUGUCUCAUACCCCUGACCAUUCGUGCGUGGCACGGAGCCGGGUAUCUGCGGGUACAGCGAUGAACAGGGCAGACGUGGCCAGGUGAGCGGCGCUGCUGAAGCCUGGUUUAACACGAAAGGCCACACUACCAUCACCCCUUUCUCCAACCCUGAAAAACAGUUCCUGAGACCUGAACUAUUGACCAUCAUUUUAAUCGGACCAACUGCAGCUGUAACAAGCUUCUCUUUGGGGUCACAAUGACCACUGCAGGCAGGGGAAAUUUAGGCCUCAUCCCCAGGAGCACUGCUUUCCAGAAGCAAGAGGGGCGCCUGACUGUGAAGCAGGAGCCAGCAAACCAGACCUGGGGGCAGGGCAGCAGUCUCCAGAAGAACUAUCCUCCUGUCUGCGAAAUCUUCCGGCUACACUUCAGGCAAUUGUGUUACCACGAGAUGUCUGGGCCGCAGGAAGCAUUGAGCCGGCUUCGGGAGCUCUGCCGCUGGUGGCUCAUGCCAGAGGUGCACACCAAGGAGCAGAUCCUGGAGCUGCUGGUGCUUGAGCAGUUCCUGAGCAUCCUCCCUGGGGAGCUCCGGACCUGGGUGCAGCUGCAUCACCCUGAGAGUGGUGAGGAGGCUGUGGCUGUGGUGGAGGAUUUCCAGAGACACCUCAGUGGAUCAGAGGAGGUUUCAGCCCCAGCACAGAAACAGGAAAUGCAUUUUGAGGAGACAACAGCUCUGGGUACAACAAAGGAAUCUCCUCCUACCUCACCCCUCAGUGGGGGCUCAGCCCCUGGAGCCCACCUGGAGCCUCCUUAUGACCCAGGGACACACCACCUCCCCAGUGGGGACUUCGCUCAAUGUACUUCUCCAGUUCCUACCCUUCCUCAAGUGGGGAACUCAGGAGACCAAGCAGGGGCAACUGUACUUCGGAUGGUCAGGCCCCAGGAUACUGUGGCAUAUGAGGACCUAUCUGUAGACUACACUCAGAAGAAAUGGAAAAGUCUCACACUCAGUCAGAGAGCCCUGCAGUGGAACAUGAUGCCAGAAAAUCACCAUAGCAUGGCCUCCUUGGGAAUGGUUGCUUUCAACAUUUUCCAGGUUGUGAAAGGUUUGCCACGAUUCUCAGGGGUGUGGUUCUAAGCUGCAUCAGUGGAACAAAUACAAAAUGCUGUCCUCCUCCCAGGCUGGAAGGCAGUGCACUUUCUCCUCUUAACAGCCAGACUAGCGGGUGAGGAGUCAGUGCUGUGACCCAGGCCAAGCUGGAGUGUCCGCAUGGCUUUUUCUCUGACCAGUGGGGAUUCCAUCUAUCUUGAGGCGUGCUGGCUGGGCCCCGUUUCCACACCAGCACAUGGUGAGACAGGGUAGCUUAUCAACAGGCUGCUGGGCCUUAAUACUGACAGUGAGUGUGGGGGGUCACAGCCAGGAAGGGACUAACACAGAUGCCCGCCCAGCCCCCACUGCUGGCCUAAUUUUAGAAUACCACGGAAAAAAGCUUUGAUGAAGACAACAGGAAGUCAACACAGCAGAGAGUGGUGUGGACAACCCAGAAGCCAGCCUCACGCAUUCCAUGCCCACAGUUAACGAUGACAACAACAGCAGUAAAACAAAGGUACAGGUGAAAAGCAGCGCUCGGGGUGUGCUGCUGCAAGCUGGGGAAGGUGCGUGCUCAACUUGGAUGGGACACACCUAGUCUUUCUUCAAGUCCCUGGAUUCAAAGAGCUUCAACCGUUCUUGCACCGUCAGGCCUUCCUUCAGACUCUUGGACCUGAUGUUUCUGAGUUGCCAGGUGACACAGGAUCUGUCUUUCUUCAAGAAGUCAGGGUUGCUUUUAGAUUUCAUUAUAUCAUAUCCGGACACCAUGGCACUGUCAGGGGACUUUUCCCCCAGUGCUUCCGUUGCAGCCUUAAGCUGCUCUUUCAACCUGCUGAUGUCACAGUCAGCCUUAGCCUUUGCGAUGCUGAGCUCUGUGUAGAUGUCUUUGUGGUGUCACUUGCGUACUUCUUGUCCCACAGUGCUGUCUGCAGCUCAUCCUUGAGGGAGCUAAUCUCCUGUUUCAGGUACUGUAUUUCCGAUUCCUAUAUCCGCAAUAAGACUUCUAGUUCAUAGGCAUCCUUGCCCUGUGCAAGGGGUGACCCAGUGGCCUCCCCACCGCCGUCCCCAGUCAGCAGCGUCCGCAACCGUGUGAUCUCUGCAGCCAGGCGGUUGUUCAGCUCCUGGUUGUGGGCAUUGAGCUCCUGGUUCUCACGCUGGCACUGCCGCAGGGCCUGCUGCCCGGCCUCCAGCGCCUGGGCCAGAUGGGCAUUCUCCAGGCACUUCUGCGAGUACUGCUCCGAGAGGACCUCCAGUUCCCGCUGCACCGACUGCAGCUCCUCCAGGUACUGGCGCCGCAGGGCCUCAACAUCCGAGUUGACGCUGCUGAUCUGGGACCGCUGGCUCUUCUCCAGCUCCCGCUCCAUCUCCUCCCGGUGGGCGUUCUUCAUGGCUUCGAUGGCUGAGAUGGUGGCCGCUGUCUCCUCGGCUAGGAGUCGGUCUUUCUCUUCUCGAAGUUUCUCUAGCUCCCGCUGGUGCUGCCUCUGGAGAUCUUCAAUCUUCUUCUGGUGCGUUUCUUCCAUUGCUGCAAACCCUCACUUGCACGUGGCCUGCAGCAUGUAGCCCUCACGGGCGCUCUGCUCCCGGCCCAGGGCCACCCUCAGCUGGUCCUGCAGGAGCCGGUUCUGCUCCAGAAGGUCUGAGGCCUCCUUCUGGCUCUGCUCCAGCUCCUUCUUGAGCAGAGAGGUCAGCUCGUGUGUGGAGAGCCGGUCACCCCCAUCUUCAGAAGACAGGUGGACGGGGACGAUGGGCACCUGCUUCUCUUCCCGGAGAGGCGUGGUCUCCACCUGAUGCCACCGCUGCUCGAUCUCCACGUGGACGUUAUGCGUCUUGAGGUCGCUCACAGGCAGCCCUGGGCUCCGGUCCACCUCCAUGCGCAGGGCUGCAUCCUCAGUGCCUGGCCCGCCUGUGGCGUCCAGCAUCCCGAAGUGCUUGCGGCGCUCCUCCCGCCUCCGUGCACGCUCCCGCUCCAGCUCCCCAGGCUCCGCCUCAGGGCGCAGGGGCUCGUGGGUGUCAGCAGGCCCCACACCGCCCACCCGCUCCUGAUUCAGGGCCUGCUGGAUGGGACGGAACUCAGCCCAGUCAAAGGUCUUGGAGAGGCCCUCUCGCCUCCGCUCCCACGUGCGGCUCCUCUUCUGCUCAGGGUCCGGCUCCCCCGGCUCUGCCUCUUGCUUCUCAGUAGGCCUCGGGCAGGUCUCAAAAGAGCAGCUGCUCUUGUUUUUUUCCUCUGGCAACCAGCUGGUCACAUCCGGGGCGGUGGUCGGGUGCACAUGCUUCAUGAUGGUCUGGAUCCAGUUCCGCCGAAUCCCAGAUGUCAUGGCCGACGGGGUAAACUCGCCCUCCUUUGUAUGUAUCUGGAAGCCAUAGUUUCUCUGAACUGGAUACUCUGUGACAUCGUAACAUGCAGACAAGUCAAUUUCUCCAUCCAAGUCGGCUGCCUCCUCAGCCACUGAAUCCCUGUAGUAUCUCAGGCUUUGAUCGGCGAGGACAAACCAGUGUUUCUUCCACUGGCUGUCCUCAUACUGCUUAGUCAGCCAGCCUUUCUUGAAAUUCAGCAGGUCGGGCGUCACGGAGGGCUCUGUGGACCUCCUGUCCAGUGACUUGGCUCUUCGGUGUGGAGACGGGGGAAGCCGAGGCGUCUGGGAGAGGAGCUUGGGGGGGGGCUUCAUUGGUGAAGUCCUGCUUGCUAGGGAACGCCCUUUUCUCGCUGCGGCCCUGGCGUGUGUCACUGGAUGGCGAGGGCCCCACUGCAUUGGUCUCCAUGUGCUCUGCCUUCUCAAUGUCCAAGGCCUCAAACUUUUCAAUCACCUGGGACCUCCUGUGGUUGGGGGUGCUGGGGCUGGGAGGGGAGAGCGGCGGGGGCAGCUGCUGUUCUUCGGCCUUCAAGUCGUGUUUGGUCUUCUCCAGAGAGAAGUAGCUGCUCUCCCCCCGGACUUUGCGGCCACAGUCCAUGCGGUCGCUACUCAUGGCGCUCUCCUCUUCUUUGCUCUCCAGCCCAGGUUCCCGCAGGGAGCUGGCAGCAGGAGGCUGGCUCUGGCUGGGACUCUGAGCUGGACUCAGACUGCUGCCAUCUGGCUGGUCCUUGGUCCUCAUUUCUUCCUGCCAGAGUGUGGACUUGGUGGUGGGGACUUUCUCAGCACUGGGGAUGCUGCUGCUGCUGCUGCUGCUGGUGGUAACAGCCACCUUGGCAGGCCCAGGCUCCUGCGGUGUGGGGGGCUCCACUUUCCAUUUCUUCUUCUGAUUCUGCUUGUUGGUCCGGGGAUAGACCAUGAGCAUCUCCAGCCACCCACUGACGAUCUCCUUGGUCUCCGCCCGGAUGAAAUGCUCCUUCUCAGGCGUCAGAAUACACAGGGAGAACCUCUGGCCCGUGCGGCCCUCCCCAUCCACCACAUCUGUGCACUGGUUCAUGUUGAUGGUGCCCUGAGGAAGGGUCGUGGGCAUCUCAUCCAGGGCGUAGCGCAAGAGGCCAUGCUCGUAAAGGAUGAAGAACUGUCGCUGCCAUUUCGGAGACCGGUGCACUGAGUUGUCAAAGUCGGUCCCAUCUGGAGCCAGGAGGAGCCAACCGCCAUAAAUGGGUUUUGCCUGCGUCAGGUCCUCGUCGUUGAGGAGAUGCGACUCGCGGGGCUGGAAGCAGUUCUGACACUUGCUCUUGUUGAAGAUGUUGGCCUGGAAUUUCCUGCACGGGUUCUCCUUGGCUGCCGACAUGGUCGGCGCGGCGGCGGCGGCGGCGCAGGCCCGGCCGGCCUGGCGCUCCCGGCGGGCUAGGGGCUCAGCGCGGCCGCCGCCGCAUCCCUCGCCGGCCCUGCCACAGGCCCUGACCGGCCUCCUUCCCUGCGGGCGGCUCGCUGCACGCGCCGAGGCUCCUGAGCCGCCCGGGCCUCACAGCGCGCGCGACGCCCAGCUCCCGCCCGCACCGCCGCCGCCCAGCCGCCGUGGGCCCAAGGACGCGGCCUCGGGCCCGCUGCUUCCCGCUGCGGCCCGCCUCUCAAGCUCCGGUCGCCGCCGUCCCGGCUCGUCCGCGCCGCCACAGCUGCCCUCAGCGCCCCGCGGCCGCUGCAAAUGACCAAUUCUUAAGAUAUGUGAAAAACCAUUCAGUUGUAGCAAACAUCAUACACCAGAGACUUUGUUUGACAUCAGAUAAAUCACACGGGUUAGAGAACUUUUUGGUUUUUAGAGGUCAAGGAAUCAUUCAUCAUGAGCUUCCAUAUUUUGCACAUAUUUCUGAAAAAUAUUCCUGAAGUGGAAAAGUUUUGUUAUACAACACAUAGUUCCUGGUACAUGAGGGAACCCACGAAAAAAGGUAUCAGUAAACAGUGUUACAGAACUUCCAA